GGUGGUCGCCGGGAGCCGCCAGCACGUGGCGGCGAGGAAGGGGCGGUGUGCUCCUGUUGUCUGCACCUGAGAGGGGGCAGGAGCUCUCGGCGCUUGCGCCUCCCGCCGCGGUGCCCUCCCGACAUGCCGGAGGAGGCGGGCUUCCCGCCGGCCAAGAGAUUCCGGCCAGGCUCUGGACCUCCGAGCCGCGCUGGGUCCUUCCCUCCCGGGAGGCAAGUGGUGAUGCUGCUGACUGCGGGCAGCGGCGGCAGAGGAGGAGGAGGAGGCCGGAGGCAGCAGCCGCCCCUGGCCCAGCCCUCGGCCAGUCCCUACCCUGAAGCUGUGGAGCUGCAGCGCCGGAGUCUGCCCAUCUUCCAAGCGCGGGGGCAACUGUUGGCCCAGCUCCGAAACCUGGACAACGCGGUCCUCAUCGGGGAAACUGGCUCUGGGAAGACAACUCAGAUCCCUCAGUACCUGUAUGAAGGAGGGAUCAGCCGCCAGGGCAUCAUUGCUGUGACCCAGCCUCGUCGAGUAGCUGCCAUCUCUCUUGCUACUAGAGUCUCAGAUGAGAAGAGAACUGAACUUGGGAAGCUGGUUGGCUAUACAGUGCGCUUUGAUGAUGUCACCUCAGAAGACACCAGGAUCAAGUUUCUGACAGAUGGCAUGCUUCUGCGUGAAGCAAUUUCAGACUCUUUGCUUCGGAAAUACAGCUGUGUCAUUUUGGAUGAAGCUCACGAACGGACUAUCCACACAGAUGUGCUCUUUGGAGUGGUGAAAGCUGCACAGAAGAGGAGAAAGGAACUCGGGAAACUUCCUCUGAAAGUGAUUGUGAUGUCAGCUACGAUGGAUGUGGACCUGUUCUCUCAGUAUUUCAAUGGCGCCCCCGUCCUCUACCUAGAGGGUCGGCAGCAUCCGAUCCAGGUGUUUUACACCAAACAGCCUCAGAAUGAUUACCUGCACGCCGCGCUUGUCUCCGUCUUCCAGAUCCACCAGGAAGCCCCUUCUUCACAGGACAUCCUGGUGUUCCUCACUGGGCAGGAGGAGAUCGAAGCCAUGAGCAAGACGUGCCGAGACAUUGCAAAGCACCUCCCAGACGGCUGCCCUGCGAUGCUGGUCCUUCCUCUGUACGCCUCCCUGCCCUAUGCACAGCAGCUCCGAGUCUUCCAAGGGGCCCCAAAGGGCUAUCGCAAAGUGAUCAUUUCAACCAACAUCGCUGAAACCUCCAUAACCAUUACAGGAAUAAAAUAUGUAGUUGACACGGGCAUGGUUAAAGCAAAGAAGUAUAACCCUGACAGUGGUCUUGAGGUGUUAGCAGUGCAGCGGGUAUCGAAGACGCAGGCUUGGCAGCGCACAGGGAGGGCUGGCAGAGAGGACAGUGGCAUCUGCUACCGGCUCUACACGGAGGACGAGUUUGAGAAGUUUGAUAAGAUGACCGUGCCAGAGAUCCAGAGGUGUAACCUGGCCAGUGUGAUGCUUCAGCUUCUAGCAAUGAAAGUCCCAAAUGUGCUCACCUUUGACUUCAUGUCGAAGCCAUCUCCAGAUCACAUUCAGGCGGCCAUUGCCCAACUGGACCUGUUAGGUGCUCUUGAACAUAAGGAUGACCAGCUUACCCUGACUCCAAUGGGAAGAAAGAUGGCAGCAUUUCCUUUAGAACCCAAAUUUGCCAAAACCAUCCUCAUGUCCCCCAAAUUCCACUGUACAGAGGAGAUCCUGACCAUUGUCUCCCUGCUGUCUGUGGACAGCGUCCUCCACAACCCUCCUUCCCGGCGAGAGGAAGUGCAAGGGGUCCGCAAGAAGUUCAUAUCCAGCGAGGGGGAUCACAUGACCCUGCUCAAUAUCUAUCGGACCUUCAAAAACCUAGGCGGAAAUAAGGAUUGGUGCAAAGAGAAUUUUGUCAACAGCAAGAAUAUGACGCUGGUAGCAGAAGUCAGAGCACAGCUGAGGGACAUCUGCUUAAAGAUGUCAAUGCCAAUCGCAUCAUCCCGAGGAGACGUGGAGAGUGUCCGCCGCUGCCUGGCUCACAGCCUCUUCAUGAGCACCGCCGAGCUUCAGCCAGAUGGCACCUAUGCCACCACGGACACCCACCAGCCAGUGGCCAUCCACCCGUCGUCUGUCCUCUUCCACUGCAAGCCGGCCUGCGUCGUGUACACUGAGCUGCUCUACACCAACAAGUGCUACAUGCGGGACCUCUGCGUCAUAGAUGCACAGUGGCUGUACGAGGCUGCCCCUGAGUACUUUAGGAGGAAGCUGAGAACCGCCAGAAACUGAGCCGCCCCAGGAUGCCGCCAGAAUCACUGGUCCCUGGGAGCUUGGACUACAGUUGUCCUUACAGCAGGCUUCCAGGUUGGCGCUUAGAGAAGCCUUGGAAUCAGCUGAAGGUGCCUGACUUCCAGGAGCGUGAAAGCAUCUUUGCUCAACUCCUGGGACUGAACCAUAUAGACAUGGACAUAUCAUUUGUACCUGGAAACCUCAAAAUUAUGCUUUUGGUUCUUACUGGGUGACUUUGACUUAAUUUAACACCUGAGCCUCAGUUUUCUCAUCUGCCAAAUGGGAGUAAUAAUAAUAAUCCUUAUAAAAUUGGGUUCAUAAAGUUUAGAGAAAAGGAAUGGAAAGUACCCAGAACUAUGCCUGGAGCACGCACGACACACGUACAGUGAGUUGGGAGCCGUUAGGCUGAAUGUUACUGCUUGCCAUAUGAUGUGAAGUACAGCAAUAUCCCAAGUUCUUGUGACUGAGGGAGAUUUUCUGGAAGGGCCACAGGAGGUUGCGGAGCUUGGAUGUUGCCCUUAGUUCUUGUUUAAUGUCUCUCUGAAUGCAGUUUUAAAAUAGAAAACAAAACUGACUUCUGUAGAAGUUUCCAGAGGGAGGUGCUGUUAUCUCGUACCUCCUGGGAUGGCGAUCCCUACUGAACGCUUGUGUCUCAGGGUGGACCACUCUGUGUCUGUCUCCAAGCAGAGACCAGUAAAGGAGCCUCCUGGUCCUCAGUGCGUGACCCUGUCAGUGCUUUCAGGAGACAUGUAAGCUUCCUGGGUGAAGGUUGAUUUGUACCUUCUGAAUCCUGUCACGUGUAGACAUGGGAAACUGACCUAUCAGUGUUUUGUGUGUGUAGGUGACUCCCACAUACACAGUUGCCAUUUUUCUCUCUAACUGGGCACCAGUGAACAUGCGGGCAUGAGGAGUGACUGUGUACCAUUUCAGCUGUUUCUUUUCGGGCAGUCCCCUGGUCAGAGGGGGUGGGGGUGGGGGAGGGGAGAGGGGUACCUAGAACCCAGAGAACAUUGGCUUAUGCCAGAUACCACACCACAUCUGGGCUUACAUUCUUGUAUCUUUUUUGGUGUGUGGGCGGGGGGGGUGGGGGGCAGUUCAGUGAAGUCUAGAAGACCUGCUGGACAAAUUCUAAAAGAGCUAGAGCUGUAACACUUAUUCUUGCAUCUUAUUAAUUUUCUAUGAUAUUUUUUCCUUCUUCGUAGGGACUUGGGACAAUCUGGCUUUGCUGCUUUCUAACUGCUAGGCACCUCUCUCUAACCCUCAUUGUCAGAGGGAAUUGGAGGAUAUCCACAGUCUGUUCCUGUUCUGAUAUUCUGAGCAGAGAAAAGGCACUAACGGUUCCUCUUAGCUAUUUAAUUAUCAGAAGCAAGUAAUCUUUCCCCAGAUAAUAUUUUGCCCUAGAAGAAGCCGUGAUUUAGCUCUUUUAUUGUGCUUACUUGGUCCAAAUACAUCUGUGGGGUGUUUUGUCAUUUCUUAAUGAAUGAAUCAUAGUUAUAACCAGGGGCCAAGCUGCCCAAGAGGCUCUUCAGAGAUCAUGGAUGCUCUCUUUCUGGAAGCUGUGGCCUGAUGGAGCAGCCCCAUUCCAGGGUCCCAUCUGUCCGGAGUUGUGUAUGUCAAGUCCGGCUCAGUCUUUAUUUCCAACACUAGCCGUGGUCCUGUGCAGUCAAGCUCUCAGCUAGUGUUUAGGGCUGUCUGUCAGAAAUGGUUAUACGUGGGCAAAAGAAGAUCUGACAGCUCCUAUAUACCUUAUCUUACUGAAUUCUUAAACUUUGAACCAGUUCUUCCACUUACUGACUUGUUACCACUGCUGACUUUCUGAAAAGUUUUCCAGUUUUUGUUUUUUGUUUUUUGUUUUCCAGUAGGGGAUUAGAAUGUUUAGUCCUACUUAGUAAGAAAAAUAUUGUAUUUUUAAUCAUUCAUAGUGCUGGUAAAAAAAAAAAAAAAAAAAAAAAAAUUGGGGGGUGGCCGGGCGCAGUGGCUCACACCUGUAAUCCCAGCACUUUGGGAGGCCAAGGCGGGCGGAUCACCUCAUGCCUGUAAUCCCAGCAUUGGGAUGGGAGGCUGAGGUGGGUGGAUUGCUUGAGAAGUUCAAGACCAGCCUGGCCAACAUGGCAAAACCCCGUCUCUACUAAAAAUAGAAAACUUAGCUGGGCAUGGUGGCACACGCCUGUAAUCCCAGCUACCGGGGAGGCUGAGGCACAAGAAUUGCUUGAACUUGGGAGGCAGAGUUUGUAGUGAGCCAAGAUCACGCCACUGCAUUCCAGCCUGGCCGACAGUGUGAGACGGUCUCAGAAAAAAAAAGAAAGAAAGAAAGAAAAAGAAAAAACUUGGGGUAAUUUAUGUCCAGCUUAAGUACCUGAACAGUUUCCGGAAAUGUAUAUUUUUUUUCUGAGAGGCAAAGGAUGUAAACAGCUUCUAAGUAGCUUUAAUGUUUCUGUACAGAAAUAAGUUUAUCCCUGUAACAUUGUGGUAGAGUUUUAAUACAGUAUUUAGUUUUUUAUUGGGCUUUUUUAAAAAGUUAACUUUUAACAUAGCUGCUCAGGGAUUAAAUCAGAUUGGAAAACCCAUUCUGACUCCACAUACUGCUACAAAGAAAUACAUCGUUGUUUAUAUUGAGCUGCAGGAGAUAGUACACUUUAAACUUAAGAAAGUUAAAUGUUUCACAAUAACAUUGCAAUAUAAUCUUCAGCUACUCUCUUUCCAUUGGUAAAAUCUCUGAUGGUGUGAUAACUCUUUGCCAACCUACGAAACCCAUAUCUGGAAGAAUCACCAGCUCCCGUGAGCAGCUUCAUGUAAAUAGAUGCACUCCAAGCAGAUUGCAUGCCUCAGGUGUUUGUCUUCUAGUAAUCAUGGAGUGUGCAACACCCAGAGUAACACUACAAGGGGCAGGACUGCAAACAGCAGGUCCUGGCUAAAAACCCUUAAUGCUGCAUUGCUGCCAGUUGUAAAGAGAUGCCUGAAUGGAGGCAAGUUCUGCCCUGUGGGUGAAACUGAUGAUGUACUGUACUGUCAUAUAUAAAUCCACUAAAUCCAGCUACCAGGAACUGCCUGGAACUGUGGCCAUGCAUUUUUUUUUUUCUUUAAAGACCAGUGUGAUAGUAGGCCAUGCAUCUGAGAUACGAUAUUCCUUGGUAACUAGAGGGAGAAAAAAAAAUCAAGUAGGUUCAGGCUUAUGUUGUAUUUUGAGAGUCUGGUUUUAUUUGAACAGAAAUAACUCUACAGAAAGCUCUUGUAAAUAAUGCUCAAAUUUGCACCCGACGAUCAAAUCCAUUAAAAAUGAAUCUUGUA